AGACGCGCCCGCUUAGCGAGGGCGCGAAGUCCAGGCCGCCAGAGCGCAGGAGCAUCCGGACCUGCUAGUCGGCCGCUGACUGCGCGGCGAGUUGCCUUGAGAGGGUCCCAUGUGCUUGGGGCGCCGCGCUGGGUCUGGGGGCGUCUUGGGGCGCCCAUUGGAGUCCGCGGGUUGGAGCAUCCGGAGAAUCCAUGAUGUGUGCAUUUGCCGAUCCCCGAGUAUGAGCCGCACAGCCUACACGGUGGGAGCCCUGCUUCUCCUCUUGGGGACCCUGCUGCCGGCUGCUGAAGGGAAAAAGAAAGGGUCCCAAGGUGCCAUCCCCCCGCCAGACAAGGCCCAGCACAAUGACUCAGAGCAGACUCAGUCGCCCCAGCAGCCUGGCUCCAGGAACCGGGGGCGGGGCCAAGGGCGGGGCACUGCCAUGCCCGGGGAGGAGGUGCUGGAGUCCAGCCAAGAGGCCCUGCAUGUGACGGAGCGCAAAUACCUGAAGCGAGACUGGUGCAAAACCCAGCCGCUUAAGCAGACCAUCCACGAGGAAGGCUGCAACAGUCGCACCAUCAUCAACCGCUUCUGUUACGGCCAGUGCAACUCUUUCUACAUCCCCAGGCACAUCCGGAAGGAGGAAGGUUCCUUUCAGUCCUGCUCCUUCUGCAAGCCCAAGAAAUUCACUACCAUGAUGGUCACACUCAACUGCCCUGAACUACAGCCACCUACCAAGAAGAAGAGAGUCACACGUGUGAAGCAGUGUCGUUGCAUAUCCAUCGAUUUGGAUUAAGCCAAAUCCAGGUGCACCCAGCAUGUCCUAGGAAUGCAGCCCCAGGAAGUCCCAGACCUAAAACAACCAGAUUCUUACUUGGCUUAAACCUAGAGGCCAGAAGAACCCCCAGCUGCCUCCUGGCAGGAGCCUGCUUGUGCGUAGUUCGUGUGCAUGAGUGUGGAUGGGUGCCUGUGGGUGUUUUUAGACACCAGAGAAAACACAGUCUCUGCUAGAGAGCACUCCCUAUUUUGUAAACAUAUCUGCUUUAAUGGGGAUGUACCAGAAACCCACCUCACCCCGGCUCACAUCUAAAGGGGCGGGGCCGUGGUCUGGUUCUGACUUUGUGUUUUUGUGCCCUCCUGGGGACCAGAAUCUCCUUUCGGAAUGAAUGUUCAUGGAAGAGGCUCCUCUGAGGGCAAGAGACCUGUUUUAGUGCUGCAUUCGACAUGGAAAAGUCCUUUUAACCUGUGCUUGCAUCCUCCUUUCCUCCUCCUCCUCACAAUCCAUCUCUUCUUAAGUUGAUAGUGACUAUGUCAGUCUAAUCUCUUGUUUGCCAAGGUUCCUAAAUUAAUUCACUUAACCAUGAUGCAAAUGUUUUUCAUUUUGUGAAGACCCUCCAGACUCUGGGAGAGGCUGGUGUGGGCAAGGACAAGCAGGAUAGUGGAGUGAGAAAGGGAGGGUGGAGGGUGAGGCCAAAUCAGGUCCAGCAAAAGUCAGUAGGGACAUUGCAGAAGCUUGAAAGGCCAAUACCAGAACACAGGCUGAUGCUUCUGAGAAAGUCUUUUCCUAGUAUUUAACAGAACCCAAGUGAACAGAGGAGAAAUGAGAUUGCCAGAAAGUGAUUAACUUUGGCCGUUGCAAUCUGCUCAAACCUAACACCAAACUGAAAACAUAAAUACUGACCACUCCUAUGUUCGGACCCAAGCAAGUUAGCUAAACCAAACCAACUCCUCUGCUUUGUCCCUCAGGUGGAAAAGAGAGGUAGUUUAGAACUCUCUGCAUAGGGGUGGGAAUUAAUCAAAAACCGCAGAGGCUGAAAUUCCUAAUACCUUUCCUUUAUCGUGGUUAUAGUCAGCUCAUUUCCAUUCCACUAUUUCCCAUAAUGCUUCUGAGAGCCACUAACUUGAUUGAUAAAGAUCCUGCCUCUGCUGAGUGUACCUGACAGUAGUCUAAGAUGAGAGAGUUUAGGGACUACUCUGUUUUAGCAAGAGAUAUUUUGGGGGUCUUUUUGUUUUAACUAUUGUCAGGAGAUUGGGCUAAAGAGAAGACGACGAGAGUAAGGAAAUAAAGGGAAUUGCCUCUGGCUAGAGAGUAGUUAGGUGUUAAUACCUGGUAGAGAUGUAAGGGAUAUGACCUCCCUUUCUUUAUGUGCUCACUGAGGAUCUGAGGGGACCCUGUUAGGAGAGCAUAGCAUCAUGAUGUAUUAGCUGUUCAUCUGCUACUGGUUGGAUGGACAUAACUAUUGUAACUAUUCAGUAUUUACUGGUAGGCACUGUCCUCUGAUUAAACUUGGCCUACUGGCAAUGGCUACUUAGGAUUGAUCUAAGGGCCAAAGUGCAGGGUGGGUGAACUUUAUUGUACUUUGGAUUUGGUUAACCUGUUUUCUUCAAGCCUGAGGUUUUAUAUACAAACUCCCUGAAUACUCUUUUUGCCUUGUAUCUUCUCAGCCUCCUAGCCAAGUCCUAUGUAAUAUGGAAAACAAACACUGCAGACUUGAGAUUCAGUUGCCGAUCAAGGCUCUGGCAUUCAGAGAACCCUUGCAACUCGAGAAGCUGUUUUUAUUUCGUUUUUGUUUUGAUCCAGUGCUCUCCCAUCUAACAACUAAACAGGAGCCAUUUCAAGGCGGGAGAUAUUUUAAACACCCAAAAUGUUGGGUCUGAUUUUCAAACUUUUAAACUCACUACUGAUGAUUCUCACGCUAGGCGAAUUUGUCCAAACACAUAGUGUGUGUGUUUUGUAUACACUGUAUGACCCCACCCCAAAUCUUUGUAUUGUCCACAUUCUCCAACAAUAAAGCACAGAGUGGAUUUAAUUAAGCACACAAAUGCUAAGGCAGAAUUUUGAGGGUGGGAGAGAAGAAAAGGGAAAGAAGCUGAAAAUGUAAAACCACACCAGGGAGGAAAAAUGACAUUCAGAACCAGCAAACACUGAAUUUCUCUUGUUGUUUUAACUCUGCCACAAGAAUGCAAUUUCGUUAACGGAGAUGACUUAAGUUGGCAGCAGUAAUCUUCUUUUAGGAGCUUGUACCACAGUCUUGCACAUAAGUGCAGAUUUGGCUCAAGUAAAGAGAAUUUCCUCAACACUAACUUCACUGGGAUAAUCAGCAGCGUAACUACCCUAAAAGCAUAUCACUAGCCAAAGAGGGAAAUAUCUGUUCUUCUUACUGUGCCUAUAUUAAGACUAGUACAAAUGUGGUGUGUCUUCCAACUUUCAUUGAAAAUGCCAUAUCUAUACCAUAUUUUAUUCGAGUCACUGAUGAUGUAAUGAUAUAUUUUUUCAUUAUUAUAGUAGAAUAUUUUUAUGGCAAGAUAUUUGUGGUCUUGAUCAUACCUAUUAAAAUAAUGCCAAACACCAAAUAUGAAUUUUAUGAUGUACACUUUGUGCUUGGCAUUAAAAGAAAAAAACACACAUCCUGGAAGUCUGUAAGUUGUUUUUUGUUACUGUAGGUCUUCAAAGUUAAGAGUGUAAGUGAAAAAUCUGGAGGAGAGGAUAAUUUCCACUGUGUGGAAUGUGAAUAGUUAAAUGAAAAGUUAUGGUUAUUUAAUGUAAUUAUUACUUCAAAUCCUUUGGUCACUGUGAUUUCAAGCAUGUUUUCUUUUUCUCCUUUAUAUGACUUUCUCUGAGUUGGGCAAAGAAGAAGCUGACACACCGUAUGUUGUUAGAGUCUUUUAUCUGGUCAGGGGAAACAAAAUCUUGACCCAGCUGAACAUGUCUUCCUGAGUCAGUGCCUGAAUCUUUAUUUUUUAAAUUGAAUGUUCCUUAAAGGUUAACAUUUCUAAAGCAAUAUUAAGAAAGACUUUAAAUGUUAUUUUGGAAGACUUACGAUGCAUGUAUACAAACGAAUAGCAGAUAAUGAUGACUAGUUCACACAUAAAGUCCUUUUAAGGAGAAAAUCUAAAAUGAAAAGUGGAUAAACAGAACAUUUAUAAGUGAUCAGUUAAUGCCUAAGAGUGAAAGUAGUUCUAUUGACAUUCCUCAAGAUAUUUAAUAUCAACUGCAUUAUGUAUUAUGUCUGCUUAAAUCAUUUAAAAACGGCAAAGAAUUAUAUAGACUAUGAGGUACCUUGCUGUGUAGGAGGAUGAAAGGGGAGUUGAUAGUCUCAUAAAACUAAUUUGGCUUCAAGUUUCAUGAAUCUGUAACUAGAAUUUAAUUUUCACCCCAAUAAUGUUCUAUAUAGCCUUUGCUAAAGAGCAACUAAUAAAUUAAACCUAUUCUUUCUGUGUGUGUGAGCGUGCGUUUGUGUUUGGUAGUGUUCCUAGGGCAGAGGUGGAGCAGGGAUGCACUUAUCAUGGGAAGGGAGGUAGAAAAGAGAAUUGGAUAGCCUGUGAUCUUUGGUGGAAUUUAUUCCUUUUGCCUAGGCCUUUCAGACCCUGCUUGAUUUCCGUAGGACACUUCAGGUUGUGGCAAGGGAGAGCUGGUCUGCAAUCGGAAGUACCAGCCUCUUCCCUAGAGCACAACUAGAAAGAAGAACUAUAGAGUGUUAUAAGGGAGGCCCUGAGAUGGAAGGACCAUCACACAGAAAUGAUAAUAACUUCAUUUCAGGGUGUUCCAGGGGAAAAGCAGGAGAAAGAUUUGGGGCUCAGUAGAAGGAAAAGCUUCCUAGUGAUAAGAGUGAUUGGCAAUACCAUGAGGUACCUUUAAAAGAUAGUGAACUCCUGUCCUUGGAAAUAUUAAACCACAGGCUAGAUAUCAUUUAAUAGGGAUGUGAAGUAGAGUAAGUCACUGCCCUUGGUGUGCAAUUGUGAACUUGUCAAUUUCUGAGGUCCCUUUCUACUUAGAUAUAUAAUACAAGAUUUCUAUUAGGUAUGGGUGCUCUGAUGAUAAUGAAAAUCCCAGCAGCUAUGUAUGGGAUGGUUACACCAGACACUGUGCUAAGGAUUUUCUUUGAAUUGUUUCUCACUCAAUCUUCACGGUAGCUCAGUGAGGUAGGUACCAUUAUCACUGCUAGAAAGCAGUGAACUUAUAUGGUCUUACUGUGGCACUGGGUCCUUAAACAUUAUGCAAAACUGUGAGCAACUUUUAUCGGUUUGUUCUUUUAAGAACAUAACACAGCACUCUAAAAAUAGAUCUAACUAGAUUGUUCACAUCUAGCGAUUAAGGCCACCCUGAGAUUAUAGCUGCAUCAUCAGGAACCCAAGAUCUGAAGCAUUCAGUCAAAGCCUCUUGGCCACCUCUCUUUUUGUCAUGGCCUUCUUGGACUUGGAGGGGGAGAAUGGAAGCAAGUACCAAGGAGAAAGUGUUCUCAGAAAAGCCACACCCAUUAGAAAAAUACAAGGCCUGAAAGGUGUGAGUGGGACUUGACACGGAAGAGCAUUUCAAGCUUAAGAAAAAAAAAAAAAAGAAGAAUGUGGGAGGAUGUCAGCAACAAUGCUUGAGAUUCCCUGGUCCCCCAAAGAGUCUCUCCUCCAUAAAACUAAUGAGAAUGUGACAAAAAUAGAUUCAACUUCUUAUAGCUCUGGAAAUUAACUGAAGAUGUAUAGCAAUUUGCAGAGCAUUUAUUCAAGAAAAAGACUAAAUCUCUGUGAGCACUGUGAUAUUGUAACUUGCACUACUCUCAUCUCCCCCUCUCCAGCUCCACAAUAGCUUUGAAACCAACAGCCUGCAAUUACCAUGAAAAUCAGCAGUCUGGCAGCCACUGAAGGUGACAGAAUGGAGUUGGAGUUCUUUCAAAGUCCCAUUCCUAGACAAUUGUCACUAUUUGACCUGUUUGGCAGGCCCUGGAAGCUCCACUUGCAAGGCUAUAUUUGACCUGACUGGAAGCUUCCCAGGGUAAAAAACUUUGUCAAAACAACUAGAGGCAAUUGAUUCUCUUUGUGGCUGCCUGGGGUAAUGUAUAACAGUUGGGGAAAGCAAUUGGCUAAAUAAAAAGCCUAAAAGGAGAAGCUGGAAAAAGAGAUUUUCAUAGGGACUUUGAAAAGCUCCAAAGUGUUAUUGGCAAUCUAGACUGCCAAAUGCAUAAAUAGGACUCCAUCCAUGCCCAGGACUGUGCAGAUGCUCAGGAAAAACCCAAGAAAGCCUUAAGCUCUCACUUCAAGCUGAUCUUGAGGCUCUGCACAAGCCAUAAGUAAAGGGAAUGCAGAGUUGUCAAUUGCAUGGCGGAGUGUUGAGUGUGCCUCAGCAUUCACACAGAGCUCCUUGGCAGAGACUGGUUGAAUUAUUGAUUCCAAGUGUUUGAGGAAAUCCGUGUACAACUAUUAGAUGACUACUAACCAAGCAGAGACUUCAGUGUCCACACACAACAAAAAAUACAGACUUUACAGAAUUAGUUCAGAAAAGUCAUUAAACAAAGAAACAACAACAAACCCUGGGGAAAUGACAGUACGAUCAAACCAUGCAUGGCCCUGCCUGCAUGUGGGAAUCCUCAUCCAAGUCAUACUUUCUAAACAUCAUAAAAAGCCCAAACCAGUCUCCUUUCCUGGCUCUCUCAAGUCAUUUUCAGACCAGGUUAGGAGACGUGAGCUGCUCUCCACAAAAAGCCUCAUGUGAGUAAUAAAUGUUUCAUACUCUCUUGGGGUGUGUGUAACAUCAUCAGUCUCAGCAUCUAAACCAAAUUUUGGUGACAUUUCAUCUUGUUUAUGCAGAUGUCCACCACACCUAUAAAUAAACAAACUACUGAAACUGAUUCAAGAAAAAAUAAAAAUCUGAAUAGAGCUAUCACAAGUAAAGAGAUUAAAUAAGCAAUCAAAUAACUUCCCAGAAAGAAAAGCCCAAUUUAGGAUGUCUUAACUGAUUAAUGUUAGCAAAUAUUUAAAGAAGAAUUGGUACAAAUUCUUCACAAACUCUUCCAGAAAUGGAAGAGGAGGAAACACUUUCCACCUUAUUUUCUAUAACUAGUAUUACCUUGAUACCAAAUUCUGACAAAUACAUCAAAAAUAAAACCAUAGACCAAUAUCUCUUUUAAGUGUAAAUGCAAAAAAAUUCAACAAAAUGCUAGAUAACUGGGUCCAACAACAUAUGGAAAGGAUUAUAUACCUUGACCAAGUGGGAUUUGCCCCAGGAAUGCAAGAUUGAUUUAACCAUCAGUGUAAUGCAUCAUAUUAAUAGAAUAAAGACAGAAACCACACAAUCAUCUCGAUACACGCAGAAAAAUCAUUUGGCAAAAUUCAACACCCCUUUGUAAUAAAAUCACUCAACACACUAGGAAGAGAAGGGAACUUCUUCAACCUCACACAUGGCAUCUAUGAAAAACCCACAGCUGGCCGGGUAUGGUGGCUCAAGCCUGUAAUCCCAGCACUUUGGGAGGCUGAGCCAGGCGGAUCACCUGAGGUCAGGAGUUCGAGACCAACCUGACCAACAUGGAGAAACCCUGUAUCUACUAAAAAUACAAAAAAUUAGCCCGGCGUGGUGGCAAAUGCCUGUAAUCCCAGCUGCUUGGGAGGCUGAGGCAGGAGAAUCGGUUGAACCCAGGAGGUGGAGGUUCUGGUGAGCCGAGAUCACGCCAUUGUACUCCAGCCUGGGCAACAAGAACAAAACUCUGUCUCAAAAAAAAAAAAAAAAAGAAAAGAAAAACCCACAGCUAACAUCAUACUUAAAGGUGAAAGACUGAAAGCUUUCCCCCAAGAGGAACUAACAGGAUAUCUGCUGUCACUAUUUUUAUUCAAUAUUAUACUGGAGGUUCUACCUAGGGUAAUUAGGCAAAAAAAAAAAAAAAAAAAAAAAACAACAACAAAAAAAAAACAAAAAAAAAAACAAACAAAAAAAAGAAAAGAAAAAAGUCAUCCAGAUUGGAAAAGAAAUAAAAUGAUUUCAAUUUUAAGAUGACAUAAUAUUGUAUGUAGAAAUCCUAAGGAAUUUACAAAAGAACUAUUAGAGCUAAUACAUGAUUUCAGCAAGGUUGCAGGAUACAAGAUCAACAUACAGAUAUAAAUUGUAUUCUACACACUUGUAAUGAAAAAUCUGAAAAUAAAAUUAAGAAAAUAGCACCCUUUGAAUAGUAUCAAAAAGAAUAAAAUACAUAGAAAAAAUGUAACAGGAAGUGCAAGACUGGUACAUUGAAAACAAUAAAACAUUGUUAAAAAAUUUAAAAUCAUCAAAAUAGAUGGAAAUAAAACCUGUGUUCAUGGAUGAAAAAAAUUAACAUUGCUCUACAGAUUCAAUACAAUUCUUAUCAAAAUCCCAGGUGGCUUAAGAAAUUGACAAGUUAAUCCUAAAAUUCAUAAGAAAUUGAAAGGGAUCCACAAUAGCCAAAAUAAUCUUAAAAAAGAUUUUAAAAAGUUGGAGAACUCACACUUCCUGGUUUCAUAACAUACACCAGGCUGGGCAUGGUGGUUCAUGCCCAUAAUCCCAGCACUUUGGGAAGUUGAGGCAGAAGGAUCACUUGAGCACAGGAGUUUGAGACCAGCCUGGACGAUAUAGUGAGACCUUGUCUCUACUAAAAAUUUAAAAAGGAAUUAGCCAGGUGUGGUAACAUGCACCUGUUGUCCCAGCUACUUAGGAGGCUGAGGCAUGAGGAUCACUUGAGCCCAGAAGAUUGUACCACUGCACUCCAGCCUACAUGACAGAGUAAGUCUCUGUCUCAAAAACAAAACAAACAACAAAAAUACUGAAAGCUUUCCCCAUACAGGAACUAACAGGAUAUCUGCUGUCACUAUUUUUAUUCAAUAUUGUUCUGGAGGUUCUAGCUAGGGCAAUUAGGCAAAAAAAGGAAAAAGAAGUCAUCCAGAUUAGAAAAGAAAUAAAAUAAUUUCAAUUUUCAGAUGACAUAAUAUUGUAUGUAGAAAUCCUAAGGAAUUUACAAAAGAACUGCUACCCUGAAAGAAUUGUUGUAAGGCAAAUACCCCUGUAAUUACCAUUAGGGGAAGAAAUUUUUCCAUGCUUCACAGAAACUCUCCUUAUACCCCACCUCAAUUUUAAUCUUUUUCUGUACCACUACAGUUAUAAUUCUCCUAAAGCUUAAAGCAAUUACCUCCUUGUUUAUAUUUAUAGUUUCAUCACUGAAGUGUGCAUUCCUAAACUCAACACCUUAGUCUGGUUGCAAACAGUUUAAAUGAGAAAAGAUAAGGCCUGAAUUAAGGCAGCAGCCCUAAACCUUUUUCUAUAAUCCUGAUAGUGAUUACCACCUAGGGGAUUAUAAAUGUUUGCUUCUUCCUCUGGCACCAACAAGUUUACUGAGCAGAAGUUUAAAAUAAUUGGAUAAUGGGGCAGGUGACAUCAGCAAGAUGUUGUAUUAGCAAAUGCUGGACCCUUCUUCAAUCCACAAACACAUCUAUUCUGCAAAAAUUCAUGGCUAAAUUCCUUUGUGAGGAAUCCAGAAACUAAAAGGCUCCUGCACUCCCAGCAAAUGCAAAAACCAGACUCACCAAAGCUGGUAGAGAGAUUUGAGAUACCACCUUGUCCGAAUCCCUAACCCCAGCACAGUGCCAUGUAGUCAGCAAGAGACUCCCUAGCACUCAGUUUCUCCCAGGUGAGAGGAGUUGGUUCACAUAUCCAAGACCUCCAACUUUUCUGAGGAGAUUCCCAGAGGACUGGCUUCUAUCUUGUCAGUCUUGGAGCUCUGACAGAAUUGGUACUAUCUAGCUACCUGGGGAAGGACAGAGACAGAGGUUUAGACCAGUAGAUGACAUGGCACCCUGCCCUCUACUGCCUCACCUCCUGGCUCAGCACAGACAGGACAAAAAUCAUGGCUACCUACAUUUCCCUGGAGAAGGAAUGAUUUGUUAAAGGCCCCCAAAUCACUGGGCAGACUUAUUGGUGGGGGUCUUCUCCUCUGAGGCCCAGCUGUGAGGACUGGGACAGGUGACUGCUUUGUCUAAUGUGCAGACACCAACACAAAGAGUCAAGGAAAAUGAAUAAUCAUACGAAGAUGUUCCAAACCAAAGAACAAGAUAAAUCUCUGGAAACUGAGCUAAUGAAAUAAACUUAUGUGAUUUACCUGACAGAGAAUUCAGAAUAGCUCUCAUAAAGAUUCUCACCAGAGUCAAGAGAACAAUGCAUGAAAAAAGUUAAGAAUUUUGACAAAGAGAUAGAGUAUAUUUAAAAGUACCAAAAAGAAAUGGAACUGAAGAACACAACAACUGAACUGAAAAAAUUUAUGACAGGACAUCAACAGGAGACAAGAUUAAUCAGAAGAAAGAAUCAAUGAACUUGAAGACAGGUCAUUGGAAAUAAUUCAGUUAGAGGAGAAAUUAAAAUGAAAAAGAGUGAAAAAAAGCCCAAGGGUCUUAUGGGCAACAUCAAGCUGAACAAUAUACUCAUUAUUGGCAUCACAGAAUAAAAGAGAGAAAAGAACUGAGAACGUAUUCAAAGAAAUAAUGGCUGAACACUUCCCAAAUAUGAGGAAGAAAAUGAACAUUCUGAUCCAAGAAGCCCAAAGGUCAUAAAAAAGUGAUCCCAAAGCCUACAGGCAUAUUAUAAGUUGUCAUCCUAGAGAAAGAAAAAUAUCUUUCUCCCAGCCUCCAUAUUCAAAUCUUAAGGAAAAUUCUUAUGGACUUAGCUUGAGUUUCAAGUUCAUUUCUAAAAUCAAUCAUGGUGGCCAAACGGAAUGAGCAUUCUGAUUUGCCAGUGUGGUCUCAUGUUACCCCUGUGCCUAGAAAGGAAACAGGAGAUGAAAAGCAUGGUGAUAAGAAGACUGGAUGGCACCACAUGGGAUAGGGGGAAAGUAGUUGAAAAAAAAUAGUUGUAAGGAAAAGAGAUACAAGGAGUCAAAAAUAACAAAUAUCUACUUAAAAGCCUUUUCCACAUUUAAUGUUUUUUGUUCACUGUGGUGUAGUAAUAAAUGUCUAUACUUAAGGGGUGAGGAUUGAUAUAUUUAAAGUGAAUGGUCUGGAAGGCAAGGAAGCUCAUUCCAACAGAUUCAUGCUACAUUGUUUAGUGACAAAUAAGGGGAACAGAACAGAGAAAGUGAUUUCAGCUAUAAAUAUAGGAGAUAAUAAAAUCCUUUAGUAAACAGUAUCUAAGCCUUGUUUUUAUGAUAUUGGGGAACAGUAACAGAUCAAAGUACUGUAGUCUUCAGUAUGCAGACCUUUCACUUUCUUAGUUUAUUCCAGGGUCUUUUUUUUUUUUGCUGCUAUUACAAAUAGCAUUGUUUUCCUAAUUUUUGUUUAAGAUAGUUCAUCGUUGGUAUAGAAAUGCCAUUGAUUUUUGUAUGUUGAUUUUGUAUCCUCCAACUUUACUGAAUUUAUUAGUUCUAACAGUUUUUUGAUGGAGUCUUUAGGGUUUUCUAUGUAUAAGAUUAUGUCAUCUGCAAACAGCAACAAUUUUACCCUUUGUUUUCAACGUGAGCGUCUUUUAUUUAUUUUUCUUGCCUAAUUGCUUUAGCUAGGACUUCCAGCACUAAAUUGAAUAGAAGUGAUGAGAGUGGGCAUGUAUGCCUUGUUUCUGGUCUUAAAGAAAAACAUUUCAGUUUUCCAUUAUUCGGUAUAAUGUUAGUUAUGGGUUUUUAAAAAUAUAUAUGACCUUUAUUAGGUUGAGGUACUUUUCCUCUAUUCUUAGUUUAUUGAAUGUUUUUCUCAUGAAAGUGUGUUAAAUUUUGUCAAAACCUUUUUUACAUCCAUCAAAUGAUUAUGUAAUUUUUAUCCUUUAUUCUGUUAAUGGAUUAUCACAUUAACUAAUUUUCAUAUCUUGAAGCAUACUUGCAUCCUAGGAAUAAAUCCCACUUUGUCAUAGUCUUUGAUCCUUUUAAUAUAAUGUUAAAUUUGGUUUGCCAGUAUUUUGUUGAGGAUUUUUGCAUCUAUAUAUUCAUCAAGGAUAUUGGGCUGUAAUUUUCUUUUCUUGUGGUGUCUUUGUCCGGCUUUAGUAUAAAGGUAAUUCUGGCUUCAUAAAAUAAGUUAGAAAGUGUUCUCUCUUCUUUGAUUUUUUUGGAAGAGUUUGAGAAUAAUUGGCAUUAGUUUUGUUAAAUGUUUGGUUGAAUUCACUAGUGAAAUUAUUUGGUCCUGGGAUUUUCUUUACUGGGAGUUUUUUGAUUACUUGUUCAAUCUUUACGCUAGUCAUAGGUCUGUCCAGUCUUUGUAUUUCUUCAUGAUUUAGUCAUCAUGUAUUCAUGGGUUGUAAGACUUAAUAUUCUUAAAAUGCCCAUAUUACCCAAAGUGAUCUAUAGAUUCAUGCAAUCCCCAUCAAAAAUCCCAGUGGCAUUUUUAUUUACAGAAAUAGAAUAAUUCUAAAAUUCAUCUGAAGCCACAAAAGACAAUGAAUAAACAAAUCAAUCUUGAAAAAGAAGAACAAAGCUGGAGGCAUUAUACUUCCUGAUUUCAAAAUAUCCUGCAAAGGUACAGUAAUCAAAACAGUAUGUUACCAGCAUAAAGACAAACACACAGACCAAUAGAACAGAAUAGAGAGCUCAGCAACAAAUCCGUGAAUAUACAGUCAACUGACAUUUGGCAAUGGUGCCAAGCAUACUCAGUGGGAGAAAUGAUAAUCUCUUCAACAAAUGGUGUUGGGAAAACUGAAUAUCCACAUGCAAAAGAAUAAAAUUGGACCCUAUCUUAUACCAAAAAUCAACUCAAAAUGGAUUAUUUAAAUGUAAGACUUGAAACAGUAAAACUCCUAGAAGUAAACAGAAGAGAAAGUUUCAUGACAUUGCCCUUGGCAAUGAUUUCAUGUACAUAACAACAAAAGCACAGGUAAUAAAAACAAAAAUAGACAAAUGGGACUACCUCAAAUUAAAAUGUUUCUGCACAGCAAACGACCAACUGAAUGAAAAGGCAAUCUAUGGAACAGAAGACACGGGGUGACAUGAGACCACUUUGGCAAAUCAGAAUGCUCAUUCCAUUUGGCCACCAUGAUUGGUUUUAGAAAUGGACUUGAAGCUCAAAGAAAGCCCAUAAUAUAUUCCUUAAGAUUUGAAUAUAGAGGCUGGAAGAAAGAUUUUUUUCUUUCUCUAGGAUGACAAGUUAUAUAUAAUAAGCCUGUAGGCCAAUAUCUGCUGGCAGCCACCUUUCCCAGGUAUAUGGAUGAAACUAUCUGAAGGAUGAAGCCUCCAUUCACAGAAAAUCAGAGCUGUAAAGGGAAGAGGAUAUCCUGAUGAAUUUUUUUCUUGGAUUGAGCCAUGUCUGAAGUCAAGCCAACUUUUGAAGUAUCCUAUAGUACUUAUAUAUUGCUUGGUAACAAAUUAUGCCAAAAUUUAGUAGCUUAAAACAACAAACAUCUAUUAUCUCAUGCAUUUCUGAUAUAGAUAUAGGAGUGACUAAUCUGGGUGGUUCUGGGUCAGAAUCUCUGGUGAGUGUGUAGGCAAGGUGUCAGUAGGGGGCUGCAAUUAUCUAAAGGCUUGCCUGGGGCUGGAGACGCACUUUCAAUGUGGUGUACUCACGUGGCUGUUGGUUGGAGGCCAAAUGUGCUAGGCAAAGCCUCAUGCACAUUUCUCUGUAAGGAAACAAAGCUGGCUUACUUGGGGGCAGGAUUUUUUUUUUUCCCAGUUGUUCUUCAAAAUGAAGUUUCCCGCUCCAAGUCCCAGCCAGAUAUGUGAAAAACAAUCCUUGCAGAACAACCCUAUUAGCAGUUCUGCAAGGAUUUUUAGGAACCGUAUUAGCAAGUUCCUCAGUUCCUCACCAUGUGAACCUCUCUUCACGACUUAGUAACUGGCUUCCUCUAGAGUGACUAAUCCAAGAGACAGCAAGGAUUGACAGCCAUGACAGCACAGUGCCUUUCAUGACUUACUCUCCAAAGUUACAAACCUUUACUUUUGCUUUAUCUUAUUUGUUAGAGCAAGUCACUAAAUUUGCCCACAUCUAAGAUGAGGGUAUUUGGGCUUCACCUCUUGAAUGGAGAAGCACCCAAAAAUCUGUGGCCUUUUUUUUUAAUUACACUCUCAGUUACAUGAAUCAAUAAAUUCCAUUUUUGGCUUAGCUUCUAUUGGGUUUCUAUCACUUGCAACCAAAGUGCCCUAACCAGUAUCUACAUCUGAGUCAUUAAGAAAGUUUCAGACAGGGCUGGGCGCGGUGGCUCACACCUGUUAAUCCCAGACUUUGGGAGGCCGAGGCAGGCGGAUCACGUGGUCAGGAGAUCGAGACCAUCCUGGCUAACACGGUGAAACCUUAUCUCUACUAAAAAUACAAAAAAUUAGCCGGGUGUGGUGGCAGGUGCCUGAAGUCCCAGCUACUCGGGAGGCUGAGGCAGGGGAAUGGCGUGAACCCGGGAGACGGAGCUUGCAGUGAGCCGAGAUCACGCCACUGCGCUCCAGCCUGGGCGACAGAGUGAGACUCAGCUUCAAAAAAAAAAAAAAAAAAGAAAGUUUCAGAUAUUAUUGUUUAUUGCUUUUAAUCUAGUGAAUUCAUAAAUCGUCACUUAACUCAAGCAAAACAAUGUUACUCUCUUUGUACAUUGUACAGAUGCAGGAUAACAAUGCAGUGUUAUCCUGCAUCUGUACAAUCAAGCACCCAAACUGGUUCUGUAGAGGCAGGACCUUAGCAUAUAGCAGAGAUAACUUAUCUUCCAGCAGAUCCGGAGCUCCAUUUUGUAGACAGAAAUGAAUGCUCUGUGCCACAGAAGGAGCUGUUGCACUAUUCAUUCCCGUUUCCUCCCAUUCACUCUCCACAUCUCCAAUCCUGGCAUUGUCUGCUUUGUUACUUGUUAAAAACUUGAUUUCGUAGAUUGCUUUAAAAUAAGAACAAAAUGUACUUUGACACACAUCAUUUUGUUUGGUUCUCAUUAAUUUUGAGAGAAAGGCAAGAUAGAUAUUUAAAUGACCCCUAUUUUAGUGGUAAACAAGCUGAAAUUAGAUAAAUAAAAUGAUUUGCCUAAUG